UUGCCCAGGCUGGAGUGCAAUGGCACAAUCUCGGCUCUCCGCAACCUCCGCCUCCUGGGUUCAAGCAAUUCUCCUGCCUCAGCCUCCUGAGUAGCUGGGAUUACAGACAUACGCCACCAUGUCCAGCUAAUUUUGUAUUUUUAGUAGAUACGGGGUUUCUCCAUGUUGGUCAGGCUGGUCUCAAACUCCUGAUCUCAGGUGAUCCUCCUGUCUUGGCCUCCCAAAGUGCUGGGAUUACAGGCAUGAGCCACCGCACCCGGCCUCAACUGGCUAAUUUGUUUUUUUUUUUUUUUUUUUUUUUUUUGAGACAGAGUCUCACUCUGUUGCCCAGGCUGAAGUGCAGUGGCACGAUCUUGGCUCACUGCAAGCUCCACCUCCUAGGUUCAUGCCAUUCUCCUGCCUCAACCUCCUGAGUAGCUGGGACUACAGGCACCUGCCACCACGCCCAGCUAAUUUUUUCGUAUUUUUAGUAGAGAUGGGGUUUCACUGUGUUAGCCAGGAUGGUCUCGAUCUCCUGACCUCGUAAUCCACCCUCCUCGGCCUCCCAAAGUGCUGGGAUUACAGAUGUGAGCCACCGUGCCCGGCUCCCUCCCAUCUCUUACAAAUUAAGAUGUUCUACGAGGAGCAUUUGCACUUGGACGAUGAGAUCCGCUACAUCCUGGAUGGCAGUGGGUACUUCGAUGUGAGGGACAAGGAGGACCAGUGGAUCCGGAUCUUCAUGGAGAAGGGAGACAUGGUGACGCUCCCCGCGGGGAUCUAUCACCGCUUCACGGUGGACGAGAAGAACUACACGAAGGCCAUGCGGCUGUUUGUGGGAGAACCGGUGUGGACAGCGUACAACCGGCCCGCUGACCAUUUUGAAGCCCGCGGGCAGUACGUGAAAUUUCUGGCACAGACCGCCUAGCAGUGCUGCCUGGGAACUAACACGUGCCUCGUAAAGGUCCCCAAUGUAAUGACUGAGCAGAAAAUCAAUCACUUUCUCUUUGCUUUUAGAGGAUAGCCUUGAGGCUAGAUUAUCUUUCCUUUGUAAGAUUAUUUGAUCAGAAUAUUUUGUAAUGAAAGGAUCUAGAAAGCAACUUGGAAGUGUAAAGAGUCACCUUCAUUUUCUGUAACUCAAUCAAGACUGGUGGGUCCAUGGCCCUGUGUUAGUUCAUGCAUUCAGUUGAGUCCCAAAUGAAAGUUUCAUCUCCCGAAAUGCAGUUCCUUAGAUGCCCAUCUGGACGUGAUGCCGCGCCUGCCGUGUAAGAAGGUGCAAUCCUAGAUAACACAGCUAGCCAGAUAGAAGACACUUUUUUCUCCAAAAUGAUGCCUUGGGGUGGGGAGUGGUAGGGGGAAGAGCUCCCACCCUAAGGGGCACACACUGAGUUGCUUAUGCCACUUCCUUGUUCAAAAUAAAGUAACUGCCUUAAUCUUAUACUCAUGGCUUGGAGUUACCUUAUAUUCAGGUAUAUGUGAUAUUUUGCCUGGUUUGUUAAAAUUGCCCCAUUUAGAUUCCUUCUAUAAUUGUUCUUAUAGAUAAGUAAUUUAUAUAUGAGCUGUGUUAGUAUUUUUUCAGUGUGAGAUCUCUGGAUUCUUUCACAAUAAAGCUGUUGAAUUUUAACAGGAGUAUUAGUACAUAAAUUUUCUACUCAACAAUUCCGAGAUAGGAUUAUGCCUAGUUUGUCAUAUCACAGAAAAACUCCAAGUUAACUUCAUGUUUUGGAAGGGCAGGUCGUUUUUAAAGUAUUUCUUUUUUUAACUGGAUGAAAAAUCUUCAUGUUAGGAUUAAUUUUCUUAAUCACCUCCACACUGUACAGAGGAAACUCAAGCCUUAAAUGUUUAAGUAAACUCUGUCUCAGUUUUAGGAUUAAAAUACCCACCGGUGGUGUGAUGAUGCCAUAUACCGCAGGGCUUGCUUCUGUCAAGUGUGACUCUAUCUCAGUAAUUAAAAUAAGUGCUGAUCUACUGAUUUUUUUUAAUGGAUUCAUUUCUAAAUGGGCAUUAUAAAUAGAGCUUGUUCAUUUUUAAGAACGAAACAUUCAUAUGAUAAACUAUCGCUUUAAAUUGCCUUUCUUGCUUCAUAUAACUUUUCCCUGUCAGGAUCCUUAGUGUUUGAAACUCCUCGUGCGGGGCUGGCCUCCUGCGGACUCUAGUUUCGCCUCCUUGAUGUGGCGCCUGGGAUUUCUUCACUUCAGAGCUGUAUUUUUACAGGCAAGAGUAAGUUCCUGGGCACAGUGGCUCAUGCCUGUAAUCUCAGCUACUCAGGAGGCUAAGGUGGGAGGAUUCUUAGAGCCUGGGAGGUCGAGGCUGCAGUGAGCUGUGAUUGUGGCCACUGCACUCCAGCCUGGGUGACAGAGCGAGACUCUGUCUCAAAAAAGAAGAAAGAGUAAGAGCUGAGGCAUAUAAUAGAAUUCUGCUAAAGCACUUAAGGUGAAAUCACAUUUUCUUUUCCCAGGAUGUUGCUCACAUCUUUCGUUUUUAUUGAGGUGUCAUUUAUAUACAAUAAAAUGUACUCAUUUUCA